CUUUCCGGUACCUGUGAGUCAGCUAGGGGAGGGCAGCUCUCACCCAGGCUGAUAGUUCGGUGACCUGGCUUUAUCUACUGGAUGAGUUCCGCUGGGAGAUGGAACAUAGCACGUUUCUCUCUGGCCUGGUACUGGCUACCCUUCUCUCGCAAGUGAGCCCCUUCAAGAUACCUAUAGAGGAACUUGAGGACAGAGUGUUUGUGAAUUGCAAUACCAGCAUCACAUGGGUAGAGGGAACGGUGGGAACACUGCUCUCAGACAUUACAAGACUGGACCUGGGAAAACGCAUCCUGGACCCACGAGGAAUAUAUAGGUGUAAUGGGACAGAUAUAUACAAGGACAAAGAAUCUACCGUGCAAGUUCAUUAUCGAAUGUGCCAGAGCUGUGUGGAGCUGGAUCCAGCCACCGUGGCUGGCAUCAUUGUCACUGAUGUCAUUGCCACUCUGCUCCUUGCUUUGGGAGUCUUCUGCUUUGCUGGACAUGAGACUGGAAGGCUGUCUGGGGCUGCCGACACACAAGCUCUGUUGAGGAAUGACCAGGUCUAUCAGCCCCUCCGAGAUCGAGAUGAUGCUCAGUACAGCCACCUUGGAGGAAACUGGGCUCGGAACAAGUGAACCUGAGACUGGUGGCUUCUAGAAGCAGCCAUUACCAACUGUACCUUCCCUUCUUGCUCAGCCAAUAAAUAUAUCCUCUUUCACUCA